GCUGUAGCCUCAGGCCUGACGGCGACUCCCAGGCUCCGGGACGAUUCUGGGCAGUGUCGUCCCCAGAGGUCGGCGGCCGUUGCCCGCUCACCAGCGACGCGGGGCGCCUGCGGGGACGGUGAGGCCCUGCUGAGGACUCCGGCCAGUAUGAGUCCCGGGGGCGGCGGCGGGGCUCAGGCCCUGGGUCUGCCCCGCGGUGUGACCCCGGCCGGUGCCUUGGUUUUCCUGGCCUUCAUGUCCUCCUAUGUAAACGCGGGGUGAUGACGGCGCCGACCUCUUGGCGCUGUUGUGAGAGUGAAGUGGGCGCGUGGUUAGACGCCAGCCACAGUUGUCUUUGGGUUAUGUCGUCAUGAAGCCGGCGCUCUACAGUUGUGUAACCUUGAACAAAUGGGUUCAGUAUCUUGGAAUUUCAGUUUUGUCAUCGUUUAAAAAAUAGAUCUGGAAAAAUGUGAACGCACACCGUGCAUAGUGGUGAAGACUGAACGAGCUGAUAAAGUUUUUACCAUUGUUUUAUGAGGAUUUUAUUUACAGAGUAAUUGAUUUUCCUCGCAGGUGGCACCUGGUAAAUGGUUAGCCCUUGCGGAGAAACACCCUGUUAGUUCCCAGGGAGAGAUUGGCGCCCUGGAGAGUGAUUACCAGUGUGCCUUUCCAUUAUGGUGUGUCACAGGUGCCGCAAGAUAAGCCUGAUUUUUCAUGACUGCUUUUUCCUGCCCUUCUGUGCCCUCAGGACACUGCCCAUCUCUAAGAUAAGAGCCUGGAAAGAGGACUCUGUUGGCUGUUGGAAAUUGCAGAGUAAUGCCUCAGGUGACAUUUAAUGAUGUGGCUAUAGACUUCACUCAUGAAGAGUGGGGAUGGCUCAGUUCUGCUCAGAGGGACUUAUACAAGGAUGUGAUGGUCCAGAAUUAUGAGAACCUGGUCUCUGUAGCAGGUCUUUCUGUAACUAAGCCAUAUGUGAUCACGUUAUUGGAGGAUGGAAAAGAGCCCUGGAUGAUGGAGAAAAAACUGUCAAAAGGUAUGAUUCCAGAUUGGGAAUCAAGAUGGGAAAACAAGGAAUUAUCAACAAAGAAGGAUAAUUAUGAUGAAGAUUCACCCCAAACAGUAAUAAUAGAAAAAGUUGUAAAACAAAGUUAUGAAUUUUCAAAUUCUAAGAAGAAUUUGGAAUAUAUAGAGAAGUUGGAAGGGAAGCAUGGAAGUCAGGUAGACCAUUUCAGACCAGCAAUUCUCACCUCUAGAGAAAGCCCCACUGCAGACAGUGUUUACAAAUACAAUAUAUUUAGAAGCACCUUUCAUUCAAAGUCUACUCUUUCUGAACCACAAAAAAUUUCUGCUGAAGGGAAUUCACACAAAUAUGAUAUAUUAAAGAAGAACUUACCAAAAAAGUCAGUUAUAAAAAAUGAGAAAGUCAAUGGUGGAAAGAAACUUUUGAAUUCUAAUAAAAGUGGGGCAGCCUUCAGCCAGGGCAAAUCUCUUACCCUUCCCCAGACUUGUAAUAGAGAGAAAAUCUAUACAUGCAGUGAAUGUGGGAAAGCCUUUGGCAAACAGUCAAUCCUCAAUCGCCACUGGAGAAUUCAUACAGGAGAGAAGCCCUAUGAAUGUCGUGAAUGUGGGAAGACUUUUAGCCAUGGCUCAUCCCUUACACGACAUCUGAUAAGCCAUAGUGGAGAGAAACCUUACAAAUGUAUUGAAUGUGGGAAGGCCUUUAGCCAUGUCUCAUCACUUACUAACCAUCAGAGCACUCACACUGGAGAGAAACCAUAUGAAUGUAUGAACUGUGGAAAGUCUUUUAGUCGUGUGUCCCAUCUUAUUGAACAUCUAAGAAUUCAUACUCAAGAAAAACUCUAUGAGUGUCGUAUAUGUGGAAAGGCCUUCAUUCAUAGGUCAUCUCUCAUUCACCAUCAGAAAAUCCAUACUGGAGAGAAGCCUUAUGAAUGUAGAGAAUGUGGGAAAGCUUUCUGCUGUAGCUCACACCUUACUCGACAUCAAAGAAUUCACACUAUGGAGAAACAAUAUGAAUGCAACAAAUGUCUGAAAGUCUUUAGUAGCCUCUCAUUUCUUGUUCAGCAUCAGAGUAUUCAUACUGAAGAAAAACCCUUUGAAUGUCAGAAAUGCAGGAAAUCCUUCAACCAGCUUGAAUCACUGAAUAUGCAUUUGAGAAAUCACAUUAGAUUGAAACCCUACGAAUGCAGUAUAUGUGGGAAAGCCUUUAGUCAUAGGUCAUCCCUGCUUCAACAUCACAGAAUUCAUACUGGAGAGAAACCUUAUGAAUGUAUUAAAUGUGGGAAGACCUUCAGCUGUAGUUCAAACCUUACCGUACAUCAGAGAAUUCACACUGGAGAAAAGCCAUAUAAAUGUAAUGAGUGUGGGAAAGCUUUUAGCAAAGGCUCAAAUCUUACUGCCCAUCAAAGAGUACAUAAUGGAGAGAAACCCAAUAGUGUGGUAAGUGUGGAAAAGCCUUUAGACUAUAUGAAUCACUAUACAUGUGAGAAAUCUUACAGAAGAGAAACUGUAUGAAGCAGUGGUUAUCAUGGUAAAUUUCCUAGAUUCUCCCUUAUUUAACAUUAGAAAAAUUUAUACUGGGGAAAGUCUUAUGAAUGUGGUGAAUAUAGGAAGACCUUUUAGCAAAGAUGCAGGCCAGUUUGUUUAUUAGACUUUAUACUGUAGAGAAAUCAUAUGAAGACCAUAAAUGUGGGAAAGCCUUUGUCAGUAUUAAUCCCUUAAUUGACAUAAGUAUACUCACACUAGGAUAAAACCCUGUACAUGUAGCAAAUGUGGGAAAGACUACAGACAAUAGGAAUCUUUUACAAACUCCUACAGGAGAGAAGCUGUAUGAAUGUAGAAAAUUUAGAAAUUGAGGGAAGUCUUCAGUUCCAAGUAUAUCCCUUAUUCUACAGCAGAGAACUCAAAAUGGAGAGAAAUCUCAUUUAAGAGAUGUAGCAAAGUGUUCACUAAGAGUGUUUAUCUUGGUACACAUCAGAAGAUUAAUGGUAGAACAACCUGAAGGAUUUAGGAGUUAUGUGUAAAUCUUUGCAGUCAUGCUAUUUGUAAACUGGAUUCUACAGGAGAGCAAAUAAACAUUAUAAUAAAAUAUGCAUUUCUUAGAGCAGUAGCUUGCAGUUUCAGUUGAGUUCUACUUAGAAAUUCUUUUUAGCUAGUGGGCAUGUGAAGAUAUUUAGUCACCCAGAGGAGCCAGUAAGUGUUAUAAUAUUGAAAAUUAAAGCUGCAAAAGAAAUAAAGUGAUGUUAAUAAAAGUUUUGGCAUCUAAUAAAAUCAUUUUGUAUAUCACAAACUCUUUCACUGUGACUAUUUCCUGUAAAAAAAAUUUCACUAAGAUUAGCCUUAGCGUAGCCUUUAGUGGGAGACUAGCAAACCUAGAGAAAAAUGACCUGCUCUUUAUACUAAGAAUAGCAGUAUUUUGAUGAGGAUUAUUCAGAGUCAAUUUCCAGUAGGCUUAAUCAAAUACAUUUCAAAAAAAUUUACUGAGCAUCACUCGUGUAUUAUUACACAGCGAUGGGAUAUAGGAAUCCAGUAGUUCUGAGCUUUAGUGGUGUGUCAAAGUCAGUAGGAGGGCUUGUUAAAGCACAGAUUGCUAAGUCUGAAUCUUAGGGUUUCUGUAUGAGUUGAUUUGAAUUUGCAUUUUUCAUGCGUUCUUAGGCGACACACUGUCCAGAAAGCACAUUUUGAUAACCAUUGUAAUAAUGAACAAAACAAAUCUGAUCUUUUUCUCGCAGGGAUGUUAUCUGACAAGAAAGAUGGAUAGCAAAUAAAUUUGAAAUAAUGGUUUACAAGUGCUAUGAGGACAUAACCAAGAAACAACAUACUACAAGAGAUCAGAGCAGGCUUAGCGAGAUGUGAUUUUUGAAAUGAAUCCUAAAUGAUGAACACUAAUUAUGUAAUGAGUACUACUCAUGUAGCCAUGUGCAUCCCUGCAUGUGCCUGUGCGUGUGUGUAUGCGGUGUGCUGGGUGUUAAUCUAGGUAAAGCAGACAGUCGAGUUCUGUCAUACUUGCUGCAGCUGGAUUCCACGUUCCCAUGUCUAGUUUCAGAUUCUGUGGCUUUGAGGUAGUGCUGCUGGCAGCAUCAUUGCAGCAACCGUCAUUUCUCUAUCCCUGAGUCAUAGUUACGGGAGUUUACCUUGAAAUCACUAGCCCAGAAGUGUUCUCAUUACUUUUACAGCCCACCUACCAAUUUUGAAAGCACUAAUUUGCAGCAAUAUAUGUCUUGAAAUAGUUAAGAGAGAUUUUGUUCUCUGCACUGAACCUUGACAGAUAAUUAUGUUUUGUAAGGAGGCAGGAUGGCUUCAAAUAUUCUAAGUUCUAGAUAAGAAAUGGAACAGUCUCACUGGCCCUGUGAUUAGAAUCCUAUCUUGUGAUUAGAAAGGUAAUGCAGAUCAAUUUGAUUUGGAGUGUAUGGACACUGAUGCAAGUGAAGGGGUGUGAUAUGGAUUAUGCUUCAGAUUUUGUUCUUUAUCUCAGGUGAGAGUAGUAAGAUAUGUUAUUUUAAAAAGGAACAUUAUGUUAUAGUUAUGAUAAUUCUGGUGUGGAAUGAGUGAUAAGGUUUCUGACUUUCAACAAAAUGUAUCUCCUCUGAUAUAUGUGCUACCUUAACAGAAAGCCAAAGCACAGAGGCAUAUUCCAAUAGCAAUUUGCAAGAGACAGUAGGUUUGGAAUGGGGUGGUAAACUUUUACUAUUUUGCAGGGAUUUUAUCUUUCAUUUGAUUUAUUUUUAAUCAUGAAAUUUAUAUUGAAAUUCUGUGAAACAUUGAAGGAUCUUUGGAAGAUUUAUAAUUAGGGAAGGGCCAGAUGUAGUGGCUAAUGUCUGUACUCCCAGCACUUUGGGAGACCGAGGCAGGAGGAUUGCUUGAGGCCAGGAGUUUGAGACCAGCCUGGGCAAUAUAGCAAAACUCAUUAGUCUGUUAAAAAAAAAAAUUACCCAGGUGUAGGCACACAUCUGCAGUCCUAGCUAUUCAGGAGGCUGAGUGGGGAGGGAUUGCUUGAGUACAGGAGUUUUAAGGUCACAGUGAGCUAUCAUCACACCACUGCUUUCCAGCCUGGACAGCAGAACACCACCCUGUCUCCAAAGUAAAUAAAUACAAUUAAGGAAGCAUGAUGUGGUAUCAGACAGUUGCAAGUAUGGAUAGACUGGCUACCACAUAUAUACUUAUGGGAUAAUGAGAGUAGCUUUCUUUUCUCUCAUUCUGUGUCCUUUCUCUGCUCUCCCAAGCAACUGGUACCACAGAGAUGAAGUAGUCCUAUAAUGCCCAGAUUUUGUUUCCACUACACAUAGUUUAAUGCUACCAUGUCACUUUGUUAUGAGAGGAUUCAUCGAAAUACCUGUGCUUUGUCAUUUAAAAAGCAUGGGCAUACACAUGAUAAUGCUUUACGUUUCUGGAUUUAAAGUGCCUUCACAAUACAGAACUAGGAAAAAGAAGGCCAUCUUUUUAAAUGAAGAUAGUUUUAAGAGAGCAAUAAGAGACUAUUACUUUGUUAUGAUAGAAGGUUGGGCUGAUGUCAUAAUGAUGUUAUGAUGUCACUGACAUCAUAUUAUUUCCUCAGUCAUACCUAUUAACCAUUUCUUGAGCAUCCACUAUGGGCUUAAUAGAUAAGAAACACUCCAUACCCUUUAAGAGCCCUGAGGUGUGUGUGUGUGAACAGCAUUAAACUUUGGAGUCAUGUUACCUGGGUUUAAAUCCAAGUUGCAUGAAUACUGGCUUUGUGUGACCUUGGACAAACUAUUUCACUGUGUCUUGCCUCAGUUUCUCCAUCUGUAAAAUGAUAAUAAAGCUAUCUCACAGCA